CUCUUUGUAGGCGAUCAGUGGGUGACCGCGGCUGCGAGGGACUUUGUCAUCCGUCCUCCAGGAUCUGGGGAGAAAGAGCCCCAUCCCUUCUCUCUCUGCCACCAUUUCGGACACCCCGCAGGGACUCGUUUUGGGAUUCGCACUGACUUCAAGGAAGGACGCGAACCCUUCUCUGACCCCAGCUCGGGCGGCCACCUGUCUUUGCCGCGGUGACCCUUCUCUCAUGACCCUGCGGUGCCUUGAGCCCUCCGGGAAUGGCGGGGAAGGGACGCGGAGCCAGUGGGGGACCGCGGGGUCGGCGGAGGAGCCAUCCCCGCAGGCGGCGCGUCUGGCGAAGGCCCUGCGGGAGCUCGGUCAGACAGGAUGGUACUGGGGAAGUAUGACUGUUAAUGAAGCCAAAGAGAAAUUAAAAGAGGCACCAGAAGGAACUUUCUUGAUUAGAGAUAGCUCGCAUUCAGACUACCUACUAACAAUAUCUGUUAAAACAUCAGCUGGACCAACUAAUCUUCGAAUCGAAUACCAAGACGGAAAAUUCAGAUUGGACUCUAUCAUAUGUGUCAAAUCCAAGCUUAAACAAUUUGACAGUGUGGUUCAUCUGAUCGACUACUAUGUUCAGAUGUGCAAGGAUAAGCGGACAGGUCCAGAAGCCCCCCGGAACGGCACUGUUCACCUUUAUCUGACCAAACCGCUCUACACGUCAGCACCAUCUCUGCAGCAUCUCUGUAGGCUCACCAUUAACAAAUGUACCGGUGCCAUCUGGGGACUGCCUUUACCAACAAGACUAAAAGAUUACUUGGAAGAAUAUAAAUUCCAGCCAGCUGUUUUUUAUCCUGGUUAGAAGAAUUUUGUGUUUUCUUUUAGCUAUGGAUCUUUGAACAUUACCCUAUGAUCGAAGAGUUUUGAGUUGGGUUUUUAGAUGUUGGUUGUCAUGGAGAAACAGGAAUCUGGUGUAUGCCAGCCAUCAUCAUCAUCAUCAUAACCCUUUGGAUGAAUUUUCAUUAUCAAGGGAUCUGGAAGGCUGUCUUCGCUCUGCUUCCCAGCUAACAAACAGAUGUGUUCCCAGAAGAUGAUGGGCAUAGGGUGUGUUUUUGCAAGUCAUUUUUCCCAUUUACGUAGAUUAUUCUUAUUUCCAAUUGAUCCUCAAUAGAUAAGAGUGCCAUUGAGCUUUAUUUUCAUCUGUCAGGCAAUUAAGAAAAAAGUAAAGGAAACAAAAAAGCUAUAAUAUACUAAGGAAAUUCUUAGAUUCUUUGGUAAAAUUAAAAGAAUCUUGGUGCAUGAAUGAUCCGGCCCUAAUCUAUCCAUCUUGCACAUUUGGGUUUUCCUGGAUCUCUCUUAAAGUGGGGCACAUCUCUGGUCUUGAUAGUCAAGGAGGAGGGUUGGGGUAAUCAGAUGUCUCAAGCAGAGGUGCAUCAUUGAGCCUGGGUAAUGGCUGAAAGUCCCCCAGAUAUCCAGUUUGAAGCUGCGUUGGGCAGGCCAUGGGUUUUAUUACGUCCAAGGCGUGACAGGCAACCAUUCUAUAACAGACCAACUCUUGGGCUUCCAGAAGACUGAAAAAAGCUAGAACAUUUACUAAUGCCAGGUGUUGCAUUUGACACUUUACAAGUAUAACCUCACUGAAAGUUCCCCACAAACAUCUGAAGUAGAUUCUGCUUUUAUCUCCACUUCAGAGACAAGGAGAUUGACACUUACACAGAUUAAAUGAUUUAAUAGUGUCGAAAGACAAAAUCACAACAAUUUCUCUUAAAGAUCUUAAUUACCUUUAUUUGCAAUUCCAGAAUUGGGUAACACUUCAUUCCAUAAAAUAGAGUAAGUGUUCCAAUUAGCUAAGCAGAAGAGGUUGGUUUUACAGCCAGAGAGGAGUAGAAGAAAGCAAAAAACAGAACCCAGAGUGGAUUGGUCCUUUCAAAGUUAAGUUCCUUGUAAGGUGGGGACAGGGAGACAGAACAAUAGAAAAGUAACUGAUUGGUUAACAUCAGGUUACUCCAGGUUACUUUUUUGUAAGGAUUACAGUAGAGGGAACUUAAUUAUCAUGCUGAUUGAAACUAGCCUGCUUGGGAAAUUAGGCUGUUACCUCUCUCCCGAUUUCUCAGAGGGUCAGAUAACAACCUAUUUUCAGUUUGGUAAAAAUCUCAGCUUGAGUGACUCCAUUUUGAUUAAAUUAGAUUUUUGGGGUCUAGUGCAAGACCUUAGUCCAAAACAAUGACUUUCUAUAAUUUUUAUUUAACAGGAGGGAAACUUGAGAUUUGAAUUCAAGCCACUCUGACUCAAAAGCCAUGGUUUUCUCACUCUUUUGUUCAUUUUCUCAAUAAGCUUGCAAAUGCUUUUAACCUCUGAUGCCUGCAGCCAGCAUGUACCUCAAUAUUGUCUGCUAGUCACAUGUAGGUAAUAUUUCAUCAUGUGGUUAAUACUAAGAGGGCUAUGACCUCUUAAUAAUGAUGCAUCUUAAUAAUGAUGCUAUUAUUGGGACUUUGAUUUCAGAAGUAAUGCAAGAUCUGCCUAAAUCCUAAUUAUCCAGCUUGGAAGAGUCCCUGACAUCUGAAUUUACACCUUUUCUUCCCUUCUUUUUUUUUUGAGACGGAGUUUCGCUUUUGUUGCCUAGGCUGGAGUGCAAUGGCAUGAUCUCAGCUCACUGCAACCUCUGCCUCCCAGGUUCAAGUGAUUCUCUCGCCUCAGCCUCCCGAGUAGCUGGGAUUACAGGUGCCUGCCACCAUGCCCAACUAAUUUUUGUAUUUUUUGUAGAGACAGCGUUUCACCAUGUUGGCCAGGCUAGUCUCAAACUCCUGACCUCAGGUGAUUCACCUGUCUCGGCCUCCCAAAGUGCUGGGAUUACAGGUGUGAGCCAUCACGCCUGGCCAUUCCUCCCUUCUUUUAAUCUCCUUUAGGUGUCUAUCCAGUGCAACCAUAACCCACAAGCUCUUCCCUAUCACUCCUUUCCUUUCUCUGGAGGUAAAUUUUAUAAAUGAUGUGUCCAUCAUAAUAGCCAUUUUACGUUGCAGAACAAACAACCCCAAACUCUCGGUGGCUUAAAACAAUAAAGAUUUCUACAUCUAUACACAUCUGUCAUAAUCACCAGGGAGGCUCUUUUAGCCACUCAGAACCAGGCUGAUGAAGCAGCUGCAGCACCUCCUCAAACAGCUGGUCUGAGGUGCUGAGCUGAUGGGCAAGGAGAAUCAGAGGAUCUCUUAGUGGUGUUUAAAUGCCCUGUCACUUCUGCUCCUGACAGAUUGGCCAGAACUCUGUAAAAUAGUGCCACCCAACCAUAAGGGGGCCAGGAAGCACAGUUCUCCCCUGUGCCAAGAAGGAGAGAAACAGAAAUGUUUGGUGAGCGGCAUGGUGUAACCACCACAUAUACCAUGCCAUAUAUAUCCUGCUUCCUUCUUUUUUUCUGCCUAGCUUGGCAAAUCUGACUUCACGUAAACUUUAUAGAACAUGUAUAGCCUCUUUAAUUCCAUUUCUCUUUCGCCUUUGUCUUCCAAAAGUUUUUCAGGUACUGCAAAACAGUGUCUCUCCUUCGUGUAAGCCAAAAGGAAAGAUCUCAAGCCUUGAAGUGAAAUAUACAUAAUUCAUCCCUCAGUAUCUUCAGGGAUUGAUCCCAGGACUCCCGCCCCUGCCCCCUCAAAAGCCCUGCCAAGGAUACCAAAAUCUGAAGAUGCUUAAAUCUCUUAUAUGAAACGGUAUAGUAUUUGCAUAUAACCGGCAUACACCCUCACAUAUACCUUAAAUCAUCUCUAAAUUACUUAAUAAUACCUGAUACAUGUAAAUACUAUGUAAAUAGUUGUUAUACUAUAUUUUAAAGGUUUGUAUUAUUUAUUAGUAUUGUAUUGUUAUUUUUUAUUGCUUUUUUUUCCCUCCCCCAAAUAUUUUCGUUCUGUGGUUGGUUGGAUCCGUGGAUGGGAAACCCACGGGUACAGAGGACUGACCAUAUUAAAGAGUUAGGGCUACUAACCUCAAAAAGUUUCUGAAUGACCGGAAGUUCUUCUGAUCUUCACAAACAUCUCUUGGGUUUUCUCACUUGCUAAAAUUAAAUCUGUCUUUUCUCCAGUGUCAAUAUUCAAGAUAAAUAAAUUAUGUUCACAUUCA